AUGCUGUCCGGUCACCGUGACAAUGCAGCUGAGGAACCCAGAACUACAUCUGGGCUGCGCGCUUGCGCUUCGCUUCCUGGCCCUCGUUUCCUGGGACAUCCCUGGGGCUAGAGCACUGGACAAUGGAUUGGCAAGGACGCCUACCAUGGGCUGGCUGCACUGGGAGCGCUUCAUGUGCAACCUUGACUGCCAGGAAGAGCCAGAUUCCUGCAUCAGCUGGAGUUUCGCUCUUGUUGCCCAGGCUGGAGUACAAUGUCACGAUCUCGGUUCACCGCAACCUCCGCCUCCCAGGUUCAAGCAAUUCUCCUGCCUCAUCCUCGCGAGUAGCUGGAAUUACAGUGAGAAGCUCUUCAUGGAGAUGGCAGAGCUCAUGGUCUCAGAAGGCUGGAAGGAUGCAGGUUAUGAGUACCUCUGCAUUGAUGACUGUUGGAUGGCUCCCCAAAGAGAUUCAGAAGGCAGACUUCAGGCAGACCCUCAGCGCUUUCCUCAUGGGAUUCGCCAGCUAGCUAAUUAUGUUCACAGCAAAGGACUGAAGCUAGGGAUUUAUGCAGAUGUUGGAAAUAAAACCUGCGCAGGCUUCCCUGGGAGUUUUGGAUACUACGACAUUGAUGCCCAGACCUUUGCUGACUGGGGAGUAGAUCUGCUAAAAUUUGAUGGUUGUUACUGUGACAGUUUGGAAAAUUUGGCAGAUGGUAAUGUUUCAUUCCAGAGAUUUAGCCACAAAGGAAAGAACUUUGAGGCCAUGGUAGCUGAGCCAAAGAACCAAUCUUCAGAAUUUUAAAUACCCUGUCACAAUACUGGAAAUAAUUAUUCUCCAUGUGCCAGAGCUCCCAUCUCUUCUCUUUCAGUUCAUUAAUUAAUUAAUUAAUUCAUGUAAAAUCCAUGCAUACCUAACCAUAGCUAAUAUUGUGCACUUAUAAUUCAAGAGGGCUCUAAGAGUUAAUUAGUAAUUGUAACUCUCUAUAACAUCAUUUAGGGGAGUCCAGGUUGUCAAUCGGUCACAGAGAAAGAAGCAUCUUCAUUCCUGCCUUUCCUCAAUAUACACACCAUCUCUGCACUACUUCCUCAGAACAAUCCCAGCAGUCUGGGAGGUACUUUACACAAUUUAAGCACAGAGCAACUGCCUGUCCCUGCUGCUAGUUUAAACAUGAACCUUCCAGGUAGCCUCUUCUUAAAAUAUACAGCCCCAGCUGGGCAUGAUGGCUCAUGCCUGUAAUCCUAGCACUUUGGGAGGCUGAGGCGGGUGGAUUACUUGAGGUCAGGAGUUCGAGACCACCCUGGCCAACAUGGUGAAACCCCAUCUCUAGUAAAAAUACAAAAAUUAGCUGACUUUGGUGGCACAUGCCUGUAAUCCCAGCUACUUGGGAAGCUGAGACAGAAGAGUCACUUGAACCUGGGAAACAGAGGUUGCAGUGAGCCAAGAUCGCACCACUGCACUCCACCCUGGAUGACAGACUGAACCCCAUCUCAAAAAAUUAAAAUAAAAUAAAAUAAAAUAACUAUAUAUAUA